CGCGCGCGCGCGCUGGAGCUCGCCUCUCGCCUUCGUGCGCCGUCGCGCCUGCGUACUUUGUUCGCCCUUUGACUCCUCCCUACUGGGCCGGAGAAUUCUGAUUGGUACAUUGCGGAGAUGGUCCCGCCCCACGUGCCUCCAAUCCCGGACUCGGACUCUGGCUUCUGCUGCUGAUGCAAGGAAUCCCCUGGGCUCCCGUCCACUCCACUGCUGACCAGCCCAUUCGCCUGUGCUGAGUCUUCCUGCAGGCCUUUCCUUGCCUCUGUGGGACCCUGUGGGGGUCCAUCCGGCUGGAGAAGAAAAGCCUCUCAUGCUAACGUUGCAGACCCCAGAGGGUGAGAGAAAGGGGGACUUCAUUCAGUCUUGAAACCUGUGUGCUCAGCCCCCAAGGCAUCAGGAAUUCUUCCUGCCCAGAGAAUCAAGGCAGCUUCAUUUUUUUCGUACCUUGGUCCUGUGUGGGUGUGGAGAUGGCCAAUGAGAAUCACGGCAGCCCCCGGGAGGAAGCGUCCCUGCUGAGUCACUCCCCAGGUACCUCCAAUCAGAGCCAGCCCUGUUCUCCAAAGCCAAUCCGCCUGGUUCAGGACCUCCCAGAGGAGCUGGUGCAUGCAGGCUGGGAGAAGUGCUGGAGCCGGAGGGAGAAUCGUCCCUACUACUUCAACCGAUUCACCAACCAGUCCCUGUGGGAGAUGCCCGUGCUGGGGCAGCACGAUGUGAUUUCGGACCCUUUGGGGCUGAAUGCGACCCCACUGCCCCAAGACUCAAGCUUGGUGGAAACUCCCCCGGCUGAGAACAAGCCCAGAAAGCGGCAGCUCUCGGAAGAGCAGCCAAGCGGCAAUGGUGUGAAGAAGCCCAAGAUUGAAAUCCCAGUGACACCCACAGGCCAGUCGGUGCCCAGCUCCCCCAGUAUCCCAGGAACCCCAACGCUGAAGAUGUGGGGUACGUCCCCUGAAGAUAAACAGCAGGCAGCUCUCCUACGACCCACUGAGGUCUACUGGGACCUGGACAUCCAGACCAAUGCUGUCAUCAAGCACCGGGGGCCUUCAGAGGUGCUGCCCCCGCAUCCCGAAGUGGAACUGCUCCGCUCUCAGCUCAUCCUGAAGCUUCGGCAGCACUAUCGGGAGCUGUGCCAGCAGCGAGAGGGCAUUGAGCCUCCACGGGAGUCUUUCAACCGCUGGAUGCUGGAGCGCAAGGUGGUAGACAAAGGAUCUGACCCCCUGUUGCCCAGCAACUGUGAACCAGUCGUGUCACCUUCCAUGUUUCGUGAAAUCAUGAACGACAUUCCUAUCAGGUUAUCCCGAAUCAAGUUCCGGGAGGAAGCCAAGCGCCUGCUCUUUAAAUAUGCGGAGGCCGCCAGGCGGCUCAUCGAGUCCAGGAGUGCAUCCCCUGACAGUAGGAAGGUGGUCAAAUGGAAUGUGGAAGACACCUUUAGCUGGCUUCGGAAGGACCACUCAGCCUCCAAGGAGGACUACAUGGAUCGCCUGGAGCAUCUGCGGAGGCAGUGUGGCCCCCACGUCUCGGCCGCAGCCAAGGACUCCGUGGAAGGCAUCUGCAGUAAGAUCUACCACAUCUCCCUGGAGUACGUCAAACGGAUCCGAGAGAAGCACCUUGCCAUCCUCAAGGAAAACAACAUCUCAGAGGAGGUGGAGGCCCCUGAGGUGGAGCCCCGCCUAGUGUACUGCUACCCAGUCCGGCUGGCUGUGUCUGCACCGCCCAUGCCCAGCGUGGAGAUGCACAUGGAGAACAACGUGGUCUGCAUCCGGUAUAAGGGAGAGAUGGUCAAGGUCAGCCGCAACUACUUCAGCAAGCUGUGGCUCCUUUACCGCUACAGCUGCAUUGAUGACUCUGCCUUUGAGAGGUUCCUGCCCCGGGUCUGGUGUCUUCUCCGACGGUACCAGAUGAUGUUCGGCGUGGGCCUCUACGAGGGGACUGGCCUGCAGGGAUCGCUGCCUGUGCAUGUCUUUGAGGCCCUCCACCGACUCUUUGGCGUCAGCUUCGAGUGCUUCGCCUCACCCCUCAACUGCUACUUCCGCCAGUACUGUUCUGCCUUCCCCGACACAGACGGCUACUUUGGCUCCCGCGGGCCCUGCCUAGACUUUGCUCCACUGAGUGGUUCAUUUGAGGCCAACCCUCCCUUCUGCGAGGAGCUCAUGGAUGCCAUGGUCUCUCACUUUGAGAGACUGCUUGAGAGCUCACCGGAGCCCCUGUCCUUCAUCGUGUUCAUCCCUGAGUGGCGGGAACCCCCAACACCAGCGCUCACCCGCAUGGAGCAGAGCCGCUUCAAACGCCACCAGUUGAUCCUGCCUGCCUUUGAGCAUGAGUACCGCAGUGGCUCCCAGCACAUCUGCAAGAAGGAGGAAAUGCACUACAAGGCCGUCCACAACACGGCUGUGCUCUUCCUACAGAACGACCCUGGCUUUGCCAAGUGGGCGCCGACGCCUGAACGGCUGCAGGAGCUGAGUGCUGCCUACCGGCAGUCAGGCCGCAGCCACAGCUCUGGUUCUUCCUCAUCGUCCUCCUCGGAGGCCAAGGACCGGGACUCGGGCCGUGAGCAGGGUCCUAGCCGCGAGCCUCACCCCACUUAACAUAUCCUGCGGGGAGGAGGAGCCCCAGGGGUGCUAGUCUGGACUGCUGGGACUCGGGCCCCUGGGGCCUCAGAGGGACCCCGGCUGCCACUGACAUAUGAAGAUUAUGGUUCUGCCAGGGCUCCCCUCCCUGCCUGUCCCCAAGUCCUCACCUCAAACUCCCUCCAAGUCCCAUGUAUAUAGGUCCUGAUGCCUUCCCAACCCCGCCCCUCACCCUGUUGCCACCUUGUUUCAUUUGUAAAAGGAAAUACAGAAACCCCCCCAA